GGGCCCUUUGUUCUGGCUCUUCUGAUGGCAGGGCGCCCCUGUCCCCCAGCUUGUGGUUCUGUGGGUCUCUCCUGGUCUCGGCCUCAGCUGCUGCCCUGAGUCUCUGUCCCUGCCCUUUCUAGGUCUCCGUCUCCCUUUCUCUGGGUCUCUGUUGCCCUCUCUCUGAGCCUCUGUCCCCCUCUCUCUGAGUCUGUGUCCCCCUCUCUCUGGGUCUCUGGUCCCCUCUCUCUCUGGGUCUCUGUCCCUCUCUCUCUGGGUCUCUGUCCCCCUCUCUCUGGGUCUCUGUCACCCUCUCUCUCUGGGUCUCUGUCUCCCUCUCUGGGCCUCUGGACCCCUCUCUCUGGUCCCUGUCCCCCCCCCCCGGUCUCUGUCCCCCUCUUUCUGGUCUCUGUCUCCCCCUCUCCCUGGGUCUCUGUCUCCCUCUCUUUUUGGGUCUCUGUCCCUCUCUCUGGGUCUCUGUCCCCCUCUCUGGUCUCUGUCCCCCCCUCCCUCUGGUCUCUGUCCCCCCCUCCCUCUGGUCUCUGUCCCCCUCUCUCUCUGGGUCUCUGUCCCCUCCGUCACUGGUCUCUGUCCCCCCCUUCACUGGGUCUCUGUCCCCUUCUCUCUCUGGUCUCUGUCCCCCUCUGUCUCUGGGUCUCUAUCCCCACCUCACUGGUCUCUGUCCCCCUCUCUCUCUGGUCUCUGUCCCCUUCUCUCUCUGGGUCUCUGUCCCCCCCCCUUGCUGGUCUCUGUCCCCAUCCCCUCUCUGGGUCUCUGUCCCCCUCCCUCUCUGGGUCUCUGUCCCCCUCUCUCUAGACCUCCCCUCAGUCUUGCUUGGCCCCUCUUCUUUUCUGGCAGCUGCUGCUCACAUCUUACCACCUGUUCUUGGGGUGGGACAGGGGAAGUUUCACCCACACCUUCCUUCCCCACCACUAACUUUUGCCUCCUGUCUUCUUUAAAACCCGUAAUUCAUACCCGAACCUUUAGCCUUCAUGGCCCUCGGCAUUACUCUAGGGUAAUCAUUGUGACUUCAUCACAAUUGAGUUCCUCUGGAAACUCUGAGAACACUCCCAUCCUCAGCUUUCCAAGAAAUCCAGCUCCUUCUCCUCCCUCAGACUCAGGAGUCCAGACCCCAGCCCCUUCUCCCUCACACCCAGGAGUCCAGGCCUCCAGCCCCCGCUCCCUCAGACCCAGGAGUCCAGGCCCCAGAUCCUCCUCCCUCAGUCCUAGGAGUCCGGGCCCCAGCCCCUCCUCCCUCAGACUCAGGAGUUCAGGCCCCAGAUCCUCCUCCCUCAGACCCAGGAAUACCCCCCAGCUCCUCUUCCCUCAGACCCAGGAGUCCAGGUCCCCAGCCCCUCCUCCCUCAGACCCAGUGGUCCAGAGUCCCAGCCCUCUCAGCUUCAAGUCCCUUGAGGGUGGGGUUUGGGGGAAGCUUGCUGAGUUCUGUGUUCCUCCAGGCCCAGAUGGGGGAACCCCGGGCUGGGGCCGCCCUGGACGAUGGCAGCGGCUGGACGGGCAGUGAGGAAGGCAGUGAGGAGGGUACCGGCGGCAGUGAGGGGGCUGGGGGUGACGGGGGCCCGGAUGCAGAGGGGGUGUGGAGCCCAGACAUUGAGCAGAGCUUCCAGGAGGCCCUGGCCAUCUAUCCACCCUGCGGCCGCCGGAAAAUAAUUUUGUCUGAUGAAGGCAAGAUGUAUGGUCGGAAUGAACUGAUCGCCCGCUACAUCAAGCUGAGAACGGGGAAGACCCGAACUCGAAAACAGGUUUCUAGUCACAUCCAGGUUUUGGCCCGAAGGAAAUCAAGGGAAAUCCAGUCCAAGUUGAAGGCUCUGAACGUGGACCAGGUUUCCAAGGACAAGGCUUUCCAGACAAUGGCAACCAUGUCCUCUGCCCAGCUCAUCUCCGCGCCUUCUCUGCAGGCCAAACUGGGUCCCACUGGUCCUCAGGUGGUCCAGGCCUCUGAGCUUUUCCAGUUUUGGUCUGGAGGAUCUGGGCCCCCCUGGAAUGUUCCAGAUGUGAAGCCAUUCUCACAGACACCGUUCACCUUGUCACUGACUCCCCCAUCUACUGACCUCCCAGGGUACGAGCCCCCCCAAGCCCUCUCACCCCUGCCCCCACCUACCCCAUCGCCCCCAGCCUGGCAGGCUCGGGGCCUGGGCACCGCCCGGUUGCAGCUGGUAGAGUUCUCAGCCUUCGUGGAACCGCCAGAUGCAGUUGAUUCUUACCAGAGGCACCUGUUCGUGCACAUCAGCCAGCACUGCCCCAGCCCCGGAGCGCCGCCGCUCGAGAGUGUGGACGUCCGGCAGAUCUACGACAAAUUCCCUGAGAAAAAGGGUGGCCUCCGAGAGCUAUAUGAUCGUGGCCCCCCCCAUGCCUUCUUCCUGGUCAAGUUCUGGGCGGACCUGAACUGGGGCCCAAGUGGUGAGGAGGCAGGGGCCGGUGGCAGCAUCAGCAGUGGUGGCUUCUACGGAGUGAGCAGCCAGUAUGAGAGCCUGGAACACAUGACCCUCACCUGUUCCUCCAAGGUCUGCUCUUUUGGCAAGCAGGUGGUGGAGAAGGUGGAGACGGAACGGGCCCAGCUGGAGGACGGCAGAUUUGUGUACCGCCUGCUGCGCUCGCCCAUGUGCGAGUACCUGGUGAAUUUCUUGCACAAGUUGCGGCAGCUGCCUGAGCGAUACAUGAUGAACAGCGUCCUGGAAAACUUCACCAUCCUCCAGGUGGUGACAAACAGAGACACCCAGGAACUGCUGCUCUGCACCGCCUAUGUCUUCGAGGUCUCCACCAGCGAGCGUGGGGCCCAGCAUCACAUUUACCGCCUGGUCAGGGACUGAAGGGGGACCCCAAAACUGGCUCACCCCCCAGAACACCCUCCUCCCAGGGAGGGUCCUCCAGCUCACCUCAUGCUUCUUAUUUGGGGAGAGGGCUGUGAUGUAAAGGGGUUGACCUCAGAGGCCUAAGCAACUGGGGCCAUCCCCCCCAUUAGAGGGGCCCCCAAAACUUGGUUGGAGAGCUGAACAGGCUGGGACUGAGGAAAGGAUAAACCCCGAUAUUGGGACCUCACAGUGGGUGUCUGAAAGGACAGAUCACUCCGGAGUAUCAGGGAUUGUGGGGACAGGAGUGAGACAACCCCCCAGGUACAGCACUGGCUUUUCUUUUCAGCCCCUGACAGGCCACCCCCACUCCUCUGCAUGUCUUGGAGAGCGCUAGUUACACAUUGGCUUGUCCCCUUUACUUUUUCCCAGCCACCCCUCCCCCUGAAAUUUCUGCCCCUCUCUACCACCCUCACUCCAUGACCUGUGAGAUCACAAAGUGAAGAUGAACCCUUUCUGUGCAGGAGCAGAGCCAGGUGGGCCCUGGACAUUUUUUUUUUUUUUAAUAUAACGAGAUAUUUAUAAGUGGGUGCUAGGGUCUUGACUUUAUCUCCGCUGCACAAGCAGUGUGUUGAACUUUCUAAUCUCAUCCCUCUCCUAAGUGAGCCCUGAGCUAGACGGUUUCCUUCCUCCCCUCUCAAAGUUUGUUUGUUUGUGUUCUGACAGAGGAUAAAGCUAUUUUACCAAAAA